GAGGCCCCAGCGCCACCUGCCCUCCACCACCUACCGCGGUUCCUCCAGCUCCCAGGGCCGCGGCCGGAGCAGCUCUGAGCGCUCGGUUCGCCCCACGGUGCCCUUAAAAGGCGCUGGCGCGAACCAACGAGUCCCUGAGGAGAGUAGGGGGACAGCUCCGGCUCGCAGAAUCCCCCCAAGCCACCCAUGGAGGGCGCAGCUCCGUGUCGUGUCUCUCUCAAAGUGUCUCUCGGACAGCGCUGUUGGGAACGAGCCUGGCGCUUUGAUUUAGGGAUGGGGGUGGUUUCCUCACUAACGAGUCACCCCCUCCAAAAUAUCGCAGAAAGUGGACGGCCCCAGUUGGAGGCACAUCUUGAAACCCGCGGGGGAGGCCAUGUCGGAAGAAGGCAAGCCUCAGACUCCAGGCUUGAGCUAGGUUUUGUUUUUCUCCUGGUGAGAAUUCGAAGACCAUGUCUACGGAACUCUUCUCAUCCACAAGAGAGGAAGGAAGCUCUGGCUCAGGACCCAGUUUUAGGUCUAAUCAAAGGAAAAUGUUAAACCUGCUCCUGGAGAGAGACACUUCCUUUACCGUCUGUCCAGAUGUCCCUAGAACUCCAGUGGGCAAAUUUCUUGGUGAUUCUGCAAACCUAAGCAUUUUGUCUGGAGGAACCCCAAAACGUUGCCUCGAUCUUUCGAAUCUUAGCAGUGGGGAGAUAACUGCCACUCAGCUUACCACUUCUGCAGACCUUGAUGAAACUGGUCACCUGGAUUCUUCAGGACUUCAGGAAGUGCAUUUAGCUGGGAUGAAUCAUGACCAGCACCUAAUGAAAUGUAGCCCAGCACAGCUUCUUUGUAGCACUCCGAAUGGUUUGGACCGUGGCCAUAGAAAGAGAGAUGCAAUGUGUAGUUCAUCUGCAAAUAAAGAAAAUGACAAUGGAAACUUGGUGGACAGUGAAAUGAAAUAUUUGGGCAGUCCCAUUACUACUGUUCCAAAAUUGGAUAAAAAUCCAAACCUAGGAGAAGACCAGGCAGAAGAGAUUUCAGAUGAAUUAAUGGAGUUUUCCCUGAAAGAUCAAGAAGCAAAGGUGAGCAGAAGUGGCCUAUAUCGCUCCCCGUCGAUGCCAGAGAACUUGAACAGGCCAAGACUGAAGCAGGUGGAAAAAUUCAAGGACAACACAAUACCAGAUAAAGUUAAAAAAAAGUAUUUUUCUGGCCAAGGAAAGCUCAGGAAGGGCUUAUGUUUAAAGAAGACAGUCUCUCUGUGUGACAUUACUAUCACUCAGAUGCUGGAGGAAGAUUCUAACCAGGGGCACCUGAUUGGUGAUUUUUCCAAGGUAUGUGCGCUGCCAACCGUGUCAGGGAAACACCAAGAUCUGAAGUAUGUCAACCCAGAAACAGUGGCUGCCUUACUGUCGGGGAAGUUCCAGGGUCUGAUUGAGAAGUUUUAUGUCAUUGAUUGUCGCUAUCCAUAUGAGUAUCUGGGAGGACACAUCCAGGGAGCCUUAAACUUAUAUAGUCAGGAAGAACUGUUUAACUUCUUUCUGAAGAAGCCCAUCGUCCCUUUGGACACCCAGAAGAGAAUAAUCAUCGUGUUCCACUGUGAAUUCUCCUCAGAGAGGGGCCCCCGAAUGUGCCGCUGUCUGCGUGAAGAGGACAGGUCUCUGAACCAGUAUCCUGCAUUGUACUACCCAGAGCUAUAUAUCCUUAAAGGCGGCUACAGAGACUUCUUUCCAGAAUAUAUGGAACUGUGUGAACCACAGAGCUACUGCCCUAUGCAUCAUCAGGACCACAAGACUGAGUUGCUGAGGUGUCGAAGCCAGAGCAAAGUGCAGGAAGGGGAGCGGCAGCUGCGGGAGCAGAUUGCCCUUCUGGUGAAGGACAUGAGCCCAUGAUAACAUUCCAGCCACUGGCUGCUAACAAGUCACCAAAAGACACUGCAGAAACCCUGAGCAGAAAGAGGCCUUCUGGAUGGCCAAACCCAAGAUUAUUAAAAGAUGUCUCUGCAAACCAACAGGCUACCAACUUGUAUCCAGGCCUGGGAAUGGAUUAGGUUUCAGCAGAGCUGAAAGCUGGUGGCAGAGUCCUGGAGCUGGCUCUAUAAGGCAGCCUUGAGUUGCAUAGAGAUUUGUAUUGGUUCAGGGAACUCUGGCAUUCCUUUUCCCAACUCCUCAUGUCUUCUCACAAGCCAGCCAACUCUUUCUCUCUGGGCUUCGGGCUAUGCAAGAGCGUUGUCUACCUUCUUUCUUUGUAUUUUCCUUCUUUGUUUCCCCCUCUUUCUUUUUUAAAAAUGGAAAAAUAAACACUACAGAAUGAGAGGUG